GUUUAGGCUAGCUUUUUUGUUUUGGAGACAGGCUCGCUGUGUCACUCAGGCUGGAGUGUAGUGGCAUGAUCUUGGCUCACUGCAACCACUGCCUCCCGGGUUCAAGUGAUUCUCGUGCCUCAGCCUCCCAAGUAGCUGGAAUUGCAGGUGCACGCCACCAAGCCCGGCUACUUUUUUUGUAUUUUUAGUAGAGACGAGGUUUCACCAUGUUGGCCAGGCUGGUCUCGAACUCCUGACGUCAGGGGAUCCAUCUGCCUCAAAGUGCUGGGAUUAUAGGCGUGAGCCACCGUGUCUGGCCUAGGCUAGUUUUUAAUCUCUCCUCGGUGUCCCUUAUUCUUGCAUAAUUAUAGAUGUCUUUGAAUAUAUAACUUUAAAAUAUUCCACUGAUUAAAAUAGAAGGUUGAUAAAUUAUGUCAGUACAGUAUUUUACUAGGUAAGUUGACCACUUUUUAUCUUCAGUGAUAUCACAGAAAAUAACUAAAUCAUUUUUCUGAGUUGAGGGAAGACAGUUUUUAGCUUACAGGAGCAAUAGUAAGUUAGUUUGCCCAGGAUGGCUGUCAGACCUCAGUCCUAUUUUGUUAUCCAGUAGAGACUCCAGCUGCUGCCCAGGAAAGGUGAGGGGGAUUCUCUUGUACUUAAAGAUGACUGUAAGAUUAUUCACAUGUAUCAUUGAUAAAUGUUUUUGUGUUACCUUUUUCCUCAUUUGACAGUUCUGAUUUUUAAUGCAAACAUUUAGUAUUUAAAAUAGGACUUUUCAUGAAAUGUUGCAAAAUUGUAAUUGGAAAGCUUGGCUAUUACAGCCAAGUGACAUAUAUCAGUUUAAACAAAUACUUCAACAUUUCAGUGACCGUAUCAACUGUUCUUCUAGAUGUCUGGUGAGAGACCUUCAAAAAUUGAAGUCAGUCUUUACAUAUUCAUAAUUCCACUAAUUUUCUUACACAUUAAUACUUUUCCUUAAAGCAUUGCUUACUUACUGAACUUCAUUUAAAUUCUUCUUGUGGUUCUGCAGAGAGCUUUUGAGCCAUCUACAUCUCAGAACUUCUUCAUUUUCUACAGUUUUAUGAAUCAUAGUACUGAGUCAUUACCACAGGGAUGCACCCUAAUUCUCAAAAGCCGAGGUCUCAGGACUGAUCUGAUUCUGGCAUGAUUAAAAUAGAAAGAGCCUUCUUUUGCCAAUUUUCUUUUUACAGUUCACACAUUUAUCUUUACUUGACCCUCUUUUAAGCUGUUUGAGAGUGAAUUAACAGGCCUAUAUUCCUCAGACUUCUCCCUUCAACGCAGCCCUUCACUGUACCCAUUUCCUGCAUUCGUUACUUGUCAUGUACAGUAUAUCAGACUUUGAUUAUCUCUGAUCCAGCAGCCUUAGUGUGGAAAAAAAACAAUCUGUUACACCCAAAAGUAAGAUUUGGGACUUCAAAUGUGGUCUGAGUUUGGAUUGUUUUCUGUAAGGAGUGGGGAUCUUUAAAGCACUUCAAGAAGAAACACUUUACGAUGGUGCAAGAUUACAGAAGCCUUAUCAGGGUUCGUAGAUCAUAGGACAGGGGUAGGGAAAAUGAGCCAUCUGGAGGGAGUCAAGACAGCGCAUUUGCGGGCUGUGAUUUGCCUUUCUCUCUUCCCUCUGUAGUACUUUUAAAGACAAACAAAAAAACCCAAACCACUGUCUUAAAGUAACUGUGAACAAAUGGAAACAGCAUAACCUGCUGUGGAAGCAUAAGCAUCUUUAGAGUAUGUUUUGAGGCCCUGGCCUGCUUCUGGGCGAGGGAUGGUAGGUGUGAGUUCCUCUGCGCCGCCUUUGCUUGUGCCCAGCUCUCUCUUCUCUCCGUGCUUCCUUUUCUCCUAUUUAACCUUUUUUCCCUUAGAUUGCUUCUCCAUUGACCAAAGAGUGGUAUAGGUAGCAGCUCAGAUAACUCCUCUGAUGCACAAGCCUCCCAGUUAAACUUACUUUAGAGAUUUGGAUUAUUUUCUAGUAGUUCAUUGAAAAUGAGGACAGGAACUGCAAAGAAAAAUCAAGGCUAACCAGAUACAGUGGCUCAUGCCUGGAAUCCCAGCACUUUGGGAGACUGAGGCAGGUGGAUCGCUUGAGCCCAAGAGUUCAACACCAGCCUGGCCAACAUGGCAAAACCCUGUUUCUACAAAAAACAAACAAACAAACAAACAAAAAUUUCAAGGCUGACCAAAGCCAUGAGGGUGAUGGGACUUGUGAAAGGACCACAUGUAGAAGUUGAAGACAAGUAGCAGGUUCUUAAGAAGCAUCCAAAUUUGGAGGGUGCCUUAUAAUUAAAAUAGCAAGUGUGAUGUCAGUGCUUGUCCAAUGUACACCCCACACACACUCACAUUCACGUUGACUCAUCCAUAUACACUCCCUUUUCUCCUUUUUCCUCCCUCCCUCUCUAUGCUACCUUUCCCACUCCUGACCACAGGGAGCCAGGACUAACUGGAAGAAGCCUUCUAUUAAUAUAUUCUUCCUUGUGGCAAUUGCAACUCAGGCCCAGGAUGACAAAUGGUGUCUUAGGCCAUUGUUAACACAGGGAGGUAGCGACCAGUUGACGUGUGAUUUUUAAAUGCUCAGUGCAGAAUAAAUGAAAUGAUGCCAUUGUCUUAAUAAAGCUGGCAGAUAGAAUUGCCUUAUAAAAUUUAUAAAAAUAGCUAUAAAAUUUUAUUAUUGCAACUUAUGUUCUACCUGUAGGCAAAAAUCUAGCCUCCUUUCAAAAUGCGACCUCCUCACCUACCCCUGUCACUUCUGUGAACCAUACACUCCAACUACACACAAUCCAUUCCCAAACAUCCACUUUCAGGAUUCUGUAUGAUUGUGCAAACAAGUAUUUUUCUUUAACAAACACACAGCACUUAGUAUGUACCAGACACUUGUGGUAGAUUUUUUACUCUAGUAUUUUUGUUUGUUCAAAUAUAUUUGGUCAAAAUAUGUUCUGCCCCUCUCUACUGAAGCCCUCCCUAUAGGGCCUCUGCAUGCCCUGUUGACAUCAGGUUUUGUUGUUUGACUUACACUAGCCACUAAAAUAUGAACAGCAGUGACAAAUGCUUCAUCCAAGCAGAAGCUUGAAGAGCCACUGCCUGGUUCCACCAUUGCUCUGUCCCCUUUGCCAUGAGAAAAGCAGGGCCCGGAGAGGGGCAGCUCCUCAGACUCCAGAAUGAAGAAGUCAAAUGGAGCAGGGCUGUACCAACAUGUAGCAUGAACAGGAAAGAAAUCUUUGUUAUAAGCUACUGAAAUUUGAUAAUUUGUUACCACAGUAUAACUUAGAAAAAGCUGACUAAUAGUACUCUUUUCUAAGCACUUUACAAACAUUAUUUUAAUUAGCCCUCAUAAAAACCUGAGGAACUACGGAAUAUUCUCCCUAUUAUAGAUGAAGAAACUGAGGCACAGGGAAAUUAACUACAGUCAUGCACUGCGUAACAACGUUUUGAUCAACAACAGAGUGCGUAUUCAGUGGUGGCCCUGUGGAUUCUAAUGGAGCAUAGGUAGAAACCUGGUGUAUGGCACUCAGUGUUGGCACUGCAGAUCAAGUAGGGGAAAUGACUGAUAUUCAGUCAUGGUGCCAGAACACUUGAUUUUCUGUAUGAAAAAAUAUAUAUAAAUGAAAAUAUAUAUCCCAUCUAGGUUUGUGUAAGUACACUCUGUAAUGUUCACACGAUGACCAGAUCACAUAACACAUUUCUCAGAAUGUGUCCUUAUCAUUAAGCAACACAUGACUGUAAUUUGCCAAGAACACCAGGUAGCUGAAAAGUAGUGGAGACAGGAUUCAAAUGUAGGUAGCAUAACUUUAGUGUCUAUGCUCUUUUUUUUUUUUUUUUUUUUUUGAUACGGAGUCUCUCACUGUCACCCAGGCUGGAGUGCUGUGGCGCGAUCUUGGUUCACCGCAAGCUCCACCUCCCGGGUUCACACCAUUCUCCUGCCUCAGCCUCCCAAGUAGCUGGGACUACAGGCGCCUGUCACCAUGCCCAGCUAAUUUUUUUGUGUUUUUUGUAGAGACGGGGUUUCACCGUGUUAGGCAGGAUGGUCUUGAUCUCCUGACCUCGUGAUCCACCCGCCUCGGCCUCCCAAAUUGCUGGGAUUACAGACAUGAGCCACAGUGCCCGGCCUAUGUCUAUGCUCUUAAAAGAUAGCUUUGCAUAACCACAUGCAGUUUCUUCCAACUAUAUCCCCUAUUUCACUCACAUAUCCCUUCUUCUAGGAAGUCUUACUCAUUUAAGUCCUGGCCCAACCCUUUUCCUGAGUCAGUCCUGACUUUAUUUAUGAGAGCUCUCCUCUUAAAUUUUUAAGUGACAGUUUAUAAUUGUUGACUAUAGGUAUGGGGUUGUGCAGCGAAUCUCUGGAGCUUAUCGCUCUUGCUUAACUGAAACUUUAUGCCUGUUGAUUUUUAACUCUCCUUUUCCCUCUGCCCCCAGCCCCUAGCAACCACCAUUUUACUCUCUGAUUCUGUGAAAUUGACUAUCUUAUAUACCUCAUAUAAGUGGAAUCAUGCAGUAUUUGUCUUUCCGUGACUGGCUUGUUUCACUUAGCAUAUAGGUCCUCAUGUUUCAUCCAUGUUGUUGCAUAUUACAAAAUGCCCUUCUUUUUGAAGGGCUGAAUAGUAUUGCAUUGUAUGCAUGGACCACAUUUUCUUCAUCCCUUUGUCUGUUGAUGGGCACUUAGGUUGUUUCCCCAUGUUGGCUAUUGCAAAUAACAUGGUGAUGACAUGAGAGUGCCGAGACCUCUUUGAGAUCCUGAUUCAUUUCUUUUGGAUGUAUACCCAAUAGUGGGAUUGCUGGAUCAUAUUAGUUCUAUUUUUAAUUUUUUGAGGAACCUCCAUACUGUUUUCCAUAGUUGCAUCAUUUGCAUUUCUGCCAACUGUGCACAGGGGUUCCAGUUUUCCCCACAUCCUAACCAACACUUGUCUUUUGGUGUUUUUUGUUUUUUUAUAAUAGCCAUCCCAGCAGGUGUGAGGUGAUACCACAUUGUGGUUUUGAUUUGCAUUUCCCUGAUGAUUAGUGACAUUGAGCAUUUUUUCAUGUACCUAUUGGCCAUUUGUAUGUCUUCUUUGGAGAAAUGUCUGUUUAGGUCCUUAGCCCAUUUUUAAAACUAGGUUAUUAGUUUUUUGGUAUUGAAUUGUAGGAGAGUCCUUUUAGUUUAUAGGAAUUCUAUGUUAUUCUUCAUAAUCUUCAGUGCCUAGCACAAUGUCUACUUGAUACACAUUCUAAAAAUAAUUUUUUAGUUUAAAAACUUAAUAUUAUCAAAAAAUAAUUUCUGUACUAUAAAACAUUAUACUACAUGAUUGUCAGGAUGCUUACAAUGUGUACUGCCUUACUAGGUUCUUGAUGUGUUCUCUAUAGUGGUAGAAUACCUGGACUGCCUAUUUUAAAGAUAGGGAGGCUGAGUUUCAGGUUGCAUGAAUGAUGGGUGGUAGAACCAGGACAAAGGCCAGGUGUUCUGCUCCAGGCCCAGUGAGUCCAGCACCUUACACUGCACAUCUCAAGGCUCUCAUCCAUGUCUCUUCCAGCCACGAGAUGCACAGACACAGUUAUUCUUAAAGUUUCCCUUAGCCACACCACUAGGAUGAGGCCCCAUUCAUCAGCAAUGGAGACAUGAUUCUGGAGGGCAAUCUUGGGUAUGAAGAGGUUUUCAAAGUCCCCAGAGGCCCUGAAAAACACAAUCGACAACUUUUUGCAGCCUUCUGUGUGCUGACCAAUAGCCAAGGAAAAUUUUUUCUCAUUAGCAGACUCUAUUUUCUUCGUAAUAUGAAGAAUGUGGCCUAUAGCUAUGCUUUCUCUUCUAAAAUCAUCAAGAUAUUUAACUGGUCCUCUCUCCAUGCUUGGUUAAAAACUCAGCUUAAACCUCACCUUCAGCAAACUCACUGUCUUGUAUUUCUUGCAUUGUCAUACUCAAUCUGAAGUAAAGAAACAUUCAGAGAAAACUUAAAGGAUAAUUUAAAGUAUAUUAGGCUGGUAUAGUAGUGUUACUGAAUAAAGGAAAAAGAAGUAGAGAUAAGGAAGAGGUUGCCAAGAAACACCCGUACUUUUACAUUGUAGAGAUUACUGGUAGAUUAUCAUGUCCGUUGCAGGACAGAACAUUUUCCCAUGGGUCUUCACAUUGUCUUUUUAUCAGGAAAUUAAAAUUUUUUCAUCAGUUUUGAUUAUCUCUUUAAACUAUAUGUAGUUUUGGUUUUUGGUUUUUCUCUCUCUCUCUGUGUGUGUGUGUGUGUGUUUAAGUGUCCAGUGUUUGUCUUCGGGGACUGACUGUGUUGAUAUUUUCCUUCUGUCUUGAUGAUAGCCUCUGGGAAGGGACUAUGGUAAAAUUAACAUGUCGUUUUGAAUUUAUUUAUUAUUUAUAAACAACAGCAUAGGAUGUUAUCAAAGGUCUUCCAUGUUAGCUUAUAUUGAUAGCUGAGAACAUUUUCAAAGCAGCAGAAGUUUUUUGUUGUUAAAAGCUUGUUUUUGUUCUGCUAAAAUCCUACCUCUUAUAAAAUUUAAAAGAUUUAUGUAUCUAUUUGAGAUCUUUCUAGAUCUUCACAUUCUUUUUUAUUAAAAGAUUCUUUUUCCCUUUUUUUGUUUAUUAAGAUGUUAUUUACAUACAAUAGAACUCACCAAUUUUAAGUGUAUAGUUCGUUGAACUUUGGUAGUUAUAUACAGUCAUGUACUCACCACCAUAAUCAAUAUGGAAAGCAGUCUCCUGACCAUGAAUGGUGGCUUCAUGCCCCAUGCUCUUUCCCCACAUCCAGCUGCCAGCCGCAGGUAACCACUGAUCUUCAUGUAAUUAUAGUUUUGCCUUUGCUGGAAUUUCAUAUACUUAGUAUUGUAUAAUAUGAAGUAUUUUGUGUUUUACUUCUUUCACUUGAACAUGAAAAUUUCACCAAUUUUUAAAAUUAAUUUUUCAUUUAUUAUUGUAUUAAGUAACAAUUAAUAGAUUAAGUAUUAAUCUAUAGUAUGGAUGCACCAUACUUUGUUUAUCCAUUCACCAAUUGGUGGACAUUUGAGUUGCUUCCAGGUUUGGAUUAUUAUGAAUAAUGCUGCUGUGAACAUCUGUGUACACAUUUGUGUGUGGACAUAUGUUUUCCUUCUUUAGGAACGGAAUUGCUGGGUCAUAUGGUAAGUGUAUAUUUGACAUUAGGAAAUACUACCAUGUUAUUUUACAAAGUGGCUCUACCAUUUUGCAUUUCCACCAUCGAUGUUUGAAACUUCCAAAUUCUCUACACCCUUGUCAACACUUGGUAUUGUCAGUUGUUUUAGCUUUAGCCGCUCUAUUGGGUGUGUAGUGGUAUCUUGUGGUUUUAAUUUGCAUUUCUCUAAUGAUUAGUGAUGUUGAGCAUUUUUUUUCAUGUGCUUAGUGGUCAUUUUCAUAUCUUUUGUGAAAUAUCUGUUCAAAUCUUUUAUCCAUUUUGUUCAUUGGGCUAUUUAUCUUCUAACUGACUUAAAAUAAUUCUUUAUAUAUUCUAGAUAUAAGCUCUUUGUUGGACAUGUUUUAUGAAAAUUGUAUUCUAAUUUGUGGCUUGUCUGUUACCAAAAAGCAAAAUUUUAAAAUCUUGAUUAAUUCAUUGUUAACUGGUUUUUAAAAUAGUUUGUGCUUUUGAUGUUCUAUUUAAGAAAUCUUUGCUAAUCCAAUGUCACAAAGAUUUUCUCCUAUAUGUUCUUCAAGAAUUUAAUAGUUUCUGCUAUUACAUUUAGGUCUGUGAUCCAGUUUGAGUAUAAUUCUUUUGAGGUAAAGGGUAAGAUUUAUUCUUUUCCACACAGAUACUCAUUUGUUCCAUUACCAGUUAUUGAAAAGACCCUUUUCUCAUUGCAUGACCUUGGCACCAAAACUCAGUUGACCAGUAUAGGUUUAUUUCUUGACUCUUUUCUUUCCCAGUUAUCUAUAUGUCUGUCCUUACGCCAAUACCACACUGCACUGAUGACUACAGCUUUAUGAUGUCCGGUCUGUGCUACGACAGCAAAAUGUUCCAGGUGCAUCAGGUGCUCUGCAUCCCCAGCUGGAUGGCAAAAUUCUUUUCUUGGACACUUGAACCCAUCUUCUCUUCUUCAGAACCCACCAGCGAAGCCAGAAUUGGGAUGGGAGCCACGCUGGACAUCCAGAGACAGCAGAGAAUGGAGCUGCUGGACCGGCAGCUGAUGUUCUCUCAGUUUGCACAAGGGAGGCGACAGAGACAGCAGCAGGGAGGAAUGAUCAAUUGGAAUCGUCUUUUUCCUCCUUUACGUCAGCGACAAAACGUAAACUAUCAGGGCGGUCGGCAGUCUGAGCCAGCAGCGCCCCCUCUAGAAGUUUCUGAGGAACAGGUCGCCCGGCUCAUGGAGAUGGGAUUUUCCAGAGGUGAUGCUUUGGAAGCCCUGAGAGCUUCAAACAAUGACCUCAAUGUCGCCACCAACUUCCUGCUGCAGCACUGAUAGUCCCAGGCCAACACUGGGACCGGACCGGCAGCCGAGUGACAGUGCGUGGUCCCCACCAUCAGAUCAGCCCGGGGACCGAGCAUCUCUGGUGCUGAUGUUCUUGUGGGAAGAGGGAGGUUCCACCGCACCCCUGCCCUCAACCGCAAGACUGUUGCCGUUUUAGUGUGGAGAUAAGUUUGCCAUUACAUUAGCAUGUAUUUUCUAUCUAUAUUUUUUAUUGGGCAUUUUCCCUAGGUUGGAGAGUCAGCACUCGUUUUGAAUGUGUUUAAAAUGCAUUAAAAUGGAAGAUUUCUGCAGGCAGUUGAAUGGCACUCCAGAUGGGGAAUUGCUGUAACCCUCUUACUGUAACAUGUCAUCUCCUGCGUCGUGAUGGGGAGAGGGUAAUGUUACUUCACAAAGGACAUGUCAGAUCCUUCUUCAUGGACUUUUUUAGUUACUGUUUUUUCUCUCAAACUUGUUUUCGAAUCUCCUGGGAGUGAGGGAGAAACAGGGAGCUGAAUCCUCCCCCAAGCUGUUCCAGGCCAGAGGACUCUGCAGUACCUUCUCCUACAUCUAGUAACAAAGAAUGGUGAUAACCAUGCACUGGUUCAAGGUUCUGGAGUUCUCCAUGAAACUUGGGUUAAUUUUGCUCAGAGUAUCCAGAGUUAGCCACUAGGCUGCGGGUGAAAUGGGAUGGAGAAGAACAACAGCAGGCUUCCUGGAGCCACAUGGGCUGACUAGGGCACUCUGUGGCUGGCCUGGCAUGGGCUCAGCCCAGGAAGAGGAGAAACGAUCCCUUGCCUGCCCCUCCCUGUGGCAGGGCUAACUGCCUGGCCCUCCUGGCUCGCAGCCAGCCAGCCCCCUGGCAGCAGGUUCUCCUCAGGGCUUGGGUCUUCAACCUGUGGCGACAGGAGGCAGGGCAGACUGUGGAGGACAGGAUGCAGGUCAGGGAGAGGGAAGGCAGGGGUGGACCGCCAUGAGCAUGAAAAGACCCGAAGCAAGUUGACUCUUGCAAUGUGCAACUGUUAUGUUCUGCAAAAUGAGCAACGAUGUAUCAAAUUGAUGCAAAUUUAGAUGUUGAUACUUACAAUAAAGUUUUUAAUGUGUUUUACUCUUCAGUAUUUUUCUAUCAGACUUGUACAAAUAAAGCCUUGUUCCAGGCUAUACAUAUUUACCAGUCAACCAAA